AUGGACAAACCAUUAAUGAUUAAAAAGGAACAAGGAAAAAGGCAGAAUAAAAUAGGUGUUAGAGGAGAUGUCAUCAAAAUGUUACAGGGGAAGCCUCUAGUAGCAGCCCUCCCGUUCCCACCUCCAAGCGUUUGCCGAACUGCUAGGUGGAGCCCGCGCCGCGGAGCCCACGAGCACUCCAUAUCCGGGUUUUGCCGGCCACCCCUUUCCCUGGCGCGAGCCCCCUCCCCGGCUCUCGGAGCUCUUGCCGCUGGCCCGCCCGACCGCUGCUCAUUCUGGCCUCCGCUCCGGCCCCGGCUGCGCCUACCCCGCGCGCAGGCUGCACGGUCCCCGCGCGCCCGCGCUCUGACCCGCUGUCUGCGCGUCGCCCCCCUCGCCUGCUGGCCCGGCACCGCUCGCUCCAGUUCCCAGGAGCGGGGAUGCAGAUGCUGCAGCUGGUCGGGGUGGGCGCCGCCGCCGCCGCCGCCGCCGCUGCUGCUGGUUUUUCUCGGACUGCUCGUUGCCUCCGCUCCGGCAGCUGCUGCCGCCGCCACCGCCGCCUGUGACUCGCCCCCUCCCCUUUCUUUCUUCUCUUUUUGCCUUGGUCCUCUUCCUACGGGUGUGCGCGCGCGCGGGUUGCACGGUUUGCUUUGGCAGGAGCUCGCUCGUGUGUGCGCGUGUGUGAGUGUGCGUGUCUGGAGAGCGCCAGUGCCUCGCUCGCUCUUGGGGAGUCGAAGAAGAGAAAGAACCGAAGAGACAGCGGCGGCGGCGCAGAGCCCGGGGCCGCGCGAUGAAGCUCCCACAUGCCCGCAGCUGCCCGGCCCGGCCGGCGAGCUAAUCAUCCACCCCACGGGCUCGGGGUUCGCCGGCCCCCGGGACGCAGCCCUCGGCGGCCGGGCGCCCGCUCUGUCUGCGCGCCCCCUCCGUGCACCGGGGAAGGAGUUUGUGUGGCUCUCGCUCCGGCUGUCCGCGGAGGUUGCGGGCUUGAGAGGGGACCCUCGGCUGGGAGAGAGCCUCGGGAGGACGAAGAGGAGGACGGUUUGGCGGAGAAGCCACCCCUGGCCCUCGCGGCUCCCCCUACCUAUUCCAUCGCUCCCGCUCCGAGGCGGAAAGGGGAGGACGUGGAAGAAGAAAAAGAAAGAGAAGGGGGGUGGGGUGGGAGAACUGGAUAUAAAGAUCGGCUGGGGGGAUGGUGGAAGAUUUUUGGUCUCUUCGGCAGCGUCUUUUCUUAAGCGGCGGCGGCAGCAGCAGCAGCAAGAGAAGGAGAAGCAGCCCCAGCUAUGACUGCCGCAUGUUAAUAGCUGCCGCUGGGUCCCUCGGCUGCUGCUGGAGACAGAGCCUGACUCCGAAGUUGUGCAACUGUGGACUGGGAGAGACAUUUGAACCCUCUUUUCUUUUCGCUCCCCUUUUGCCCCCUUGGGGUGUGUGAAGCGAGGAACGUAAAGGAAGGCGAACAUUUGGCUCUCUUUUUCCUUCCCCUUUCUCCGUGGCUGUGUAGCGGAAGAAAGGGAAGAGAGACUUUUUGUUGUUGUUUCCUUGACUGGGGUCUCCACCCUCCUGCUGCUUUCUCUGCGCUUCGAUUCUCGUUAUUUGCCGCGUGUGGUUGGGGGUGUCUGCACAGGGGCCGGCCGGUCUUUUGCCCCGGGCUCAAUGGCUGGAUUGUGGAAACUGCACCCGCCUUCAGGUUGUUGAGCAACUGAUGGGACGAUCUCAGGGACCGGCGUUUACGAAAGAAUGAGUAGGACAUUCAUUACCAGACCCCUUGACUGUCUCAAACCUUUAGGUUGUUGACUCAGUGUGCUUAUUGGAGGUAGGUAACCAGUAUUCUCUUACUCCAUUGACAAACAUGGGUUCUCAUUUGUUGGGAAAAAAGAGAGGAAAGUCUUUGUACCAAAGACUUACACCAAGAGGAAUUGUUGUCUGAUUUCCAAACAGGCCAGGGAAUAUACUGUGUUGCAGGAUCCCCUUGGGUAUUCAUUAAAGCAUAGUGACUGUGUCACAGGGGUGAGAGCCUAGAGAGCUGACAUGGACCUAUUUUGUAAUAUGUGCACAACUUUGUUUGUAUGUUCAGUUCCACACACACACACACACACACAUAUAUACAUAUAUAUAUAGGAUUAAGUAUAUUUAUAGCCUUUCCAAUCAAUACCAUUUGUAUUACAAAUUUAUUUCUAGAAUUACUUUGUACUUUAUAAUGAAAGUGAGCUUCAAAGGCUUUGAAAUUUUGCAUAUAAGUUAGUAAAUUGUUAUCUCUGUGAGAGUUGCACCAGAUGAUCUCUAAAUGCUCUUGCAGCUCUAAAUCCCUAUGAUUCUGUGAACCACGAUUAUUUUUUCCCAAAUUAAGCCUCCACCUAUAUGAUUUUUGGCCUUUGCUUAAUUCUGAGUGUAUACAUCUUUAUCAAAAUACUGUACAAGCAGUCAAGUCGCAUUAUCAAUAAUCAGUAGUUGAGAAAAAGAAAGCUUGCUAAUUUGGGCUUUUUUCAUAUUAACCACUGCUCAAACUCAUUAUGCAUUAUUUCUUUUUCAGUUAGAGGAGUUCAUUUACAUUCAGCAUCUUUGGGUUAAGUCAAGGUGAAAAAGCAUUCACCGUACAGUCCCCAAUUCACUUCCAUCUUCUAGAAUUGUGAGUCAUUUUUUUAGAAGUUUUAAAAUGGGGAUUGUAAACUCAGAAGCCUCAUGGGUCAGGUAGGUGUCAUUAAUGAGUUAGGGAUAUAGUGUGUAAAUGUUGCCAGAACCUCACAUUAUUUUUUAAGAAACUAUUAGUCCAGAUUUUUCUUAUGAAAGUUUCUACCUUCUUAGUGCUAUUUGAAAUUAUUUUAAAAUCUUGAAUGCUAAAGAGAUAAAUAAAUAAGAAUGACAUGACUGUGCAUGACCAGGUCUCUUCAUUCUUUAACUUCUACCUGAAAACCAGGCAUACUCUUCAACAUCAUGCUGCUAGAUAUUCUGUUGUGAAUCACUUACCCUUAUAGAUCCCUCCUCUUGGGGAUUUCCACUUACUCCCUCACUGCACGGUUGUACAAGUGUGAACAUGCCUGGAAACUAUAAUUAUCUGUGGAUUUUGACAAAAGAUCCUCAGUAGUUGUUACCAUGCUUAUUAAGUUCCCGAACAAAUUUUUAUCUCCUAAAUUAACAUCAGGUUGACAGGCAUCCAGGAUGGAUGCUGAUUCUCUGGUUAUCUGCACACUCGAAACUUAGUUUUAUCAGUCAUUUUUCUUCCUUGUGGAUCACCUCAGAACCUUUUACAUUUUUUCCAGUUUAUUUUUUGUCUUUCAGUAUCAUCCCUGCUGUUGACCCAGUGCACACCACAGCACCAAUGGCUUCCUUCAUUCUUAUGUCUUUUAAUUUUUUUUCAAGUAAUUUCAUAAUAUGACACUCUUGUACUUUUUUCAUCACUGAAAGAAUAGGAUGGAUAAUGUACACAAACUAACUCAAAUUGCAGCAUAAAUAUCAUGAACAUACAUUAGAUUAAAAGAUGUUGCUAUGGCUGACAUUAGAAUGACAUCUCCUGACUGCUAAAUUCAUUUGUUGCUGACAGUCAGGGUUGGUUGAUAUCCCGUUGUUCUUGAACACAGACUUGCUCACUUCAGUGAAAAUUUUAAGGCAGAAAGUUCUCAAGAGCUGCUGUCUGAAGCAAAUCUUAUGGCCAGAAGUUAUAGUAUAUUCAGACUGAUGCGCUAGAGUUUUCGAAAUGAUUCAUUUGGUCUUCUUAUGAAAUAGUUUUGAGAUUCUUCUUAGUAAACAUUGGCUUGAUUUUGUUUCUGUAAAAUUUUUUUUUCUUCUCCGCUGUAUGGAGAAGACUGUCAUGAGUGAACUUGGCAAUUGCCUUGUUAAAACCAGUUGGACGUUAUCUUCCACAUUGCGAAGCUAUACAUGUCUGAUAUGUUCUGAAAGAAUAGAAUUUAUAGUUAGAUAUACUAUUUUUGAUUAUUUACUCAGAAGGAGACAUGUAAUUAUUCUUAUGUUGUCAUGAAAAUCUAUUAAAUGCAUUUAUAUUUCACAUCAAUGUUACGAAAUUCCAUUAUUAUUAUUUUACAGAGGGGAAGCCAAGAUACAGGAGUGGAAAUUACUUGGCCACAUCGCACAGGUAGGAAAUUAGUCUUGGAAGUUUAACACAGAAAUCUCAUUCUUAACCACUAUCCUGUCUGCCUCUCAUUAUUUCAUUUGAAAUAGCUCACGGUUAGUGUAGGCAGGGUCCAAUAAAUUGUUUCCUAGCACCAUACAAAUCAAUCCCUAGUAAGUUGUUAUGGAAGAUUUUGUAAGAAUAGUGUAAAGCUCCUCUGUUGAUAUUUUGAAGAAUUUACUGUUCUCCUCUUUUGCAAAGUGAAUAUGCAUGUGUCUGCGUCAGCCUGCAGUCUUCUGGCCCCUCCCCAAUCUUUUAAGUUCCUUCAAAGAUUGCUGCAGUUGUUGGAUCUACUUUGCACGUCCUUUCAAAAAAUAUGGUCUUUAGUCAAAGGGUCCAGGGGACUGAAACACUUUUUCAGUGAAUAAAAAAGUUUUCAUUUCUCAAAACACAUUUUUUAAGCAUUAACUUUACUUUUCCUUCUGAUAAGUUUUUCUUCUGUUCUUUUCAAUCAGGUGGCCAUUCUCUUUACAGAAAAUUCUGAGACAACAUAACAAUUGGUUGUUUAGCUGUUUUUAAUCAUUUUUUUCUUUAUCCUUUACUUUUUACACCAUUAAUCUCAAAAUGUAUGCCUCUUCUUUCCUUGUUAUGUGUGUAUUUAAGUAUUGAUUUAAACUGUAGCAGCAUUUGUUGGAUAAUUAGGAAUUUUAAAACUCAUCAGAAGUUAUCUUUCUGCAAAGCUGGCUAGAAUUGAUGAAAACGGUGAGUUUUUUUCUGAACUGGUAACAAUAAUACAAUAAUUAUCCUUUUUUUUUCUCAGUAUGAGCCAGUAAAAGGACUUGACAUUUUCAAGAACAUCAUUUAAAUCCUUCAAGAUAAAUUUUCGGAGAUUAGCAUCUGUUGUUUGUUUGUUUAUUUUGUGUGAAGAAGUAUUGUGAGUGAAUGAAUACCAAAUCAAACACAGAAAGCGCAUUUUCACUUUUGCCUUACGAAUGAUUCGCUUUAUGUUAAUUUUUACCUUCUAUCAAGUAUAAUCUGGAAAUAAACUGAGUUUAUAAACUCUAAGGAUGAUUGCAGACAUCCAGGUUAAAAUCACAUUUUAAAAAUGUGGUUAAAUUUGCAGUGCAUUUGACUAACUGUAGUCUCAUAUCCUACUUUUAUUAGUGGAAAAAGAAUCUGUGCCUUUGAAAAACUAAAUUCAAUAUUUCCUACAAAAAUGCCAACAGUUUUUUUGAUUCUCUUUCUUAUUUCUUAUACUUGAGGUCUUUUAUGCACAUACUUAACACACACACAUAAAAUCAAAUUUUAGCAUGAAUUGAAACAUGAAAAUUAUAACACAGUAUUUCCCAGCUGAACACAAAAGUAUGCUGAAAAAUCUUAAUGUACAUUCCACAAAGCCAAUGAUAAAUCUUGCCCAUAGUUCUUAGAGGCAGUUUCAUUGUAAAAUAUUUUCCAUGAUUUUAUUUCACCUUCCAAUAUUUUGAAUUCUUCAGGAUCAAAAUGUGGUAUUUCUAUUAAAUCCAUAUUCCCAAGUCUAUCACUGACACAUUUGCCCUCCUAUGAAUAAUAUCACUGUAGUCUGUGAUAGAUCACAAUGUCAAGAAACUGAUCUUGUUUCAAUUUUUAACUCUGUUGAAAGAAAUAAAAAAUUCCAUUUGCUUCCAAGUUGUGGAGAGAAGAAAGAAGACAAUUAUUCAAAACAAUAGCUUUAACAUAAUAUUUAUUUAUGGUUUCUAAUUAGUUCUGUUGAUUAUUAUUCUUAAAACCACAAUAAUCCUUUGGUAGCAAGUAUAUGUUGUGUGGGCCAGUGAACCUAUUUGUUUAAGUCCAUAGACAAGAUGUGUAUUUAAGAAGAUUAGGGUUCUUUGAACAUAGUAUUAGACAUACUAAAUAGGUAGCUCAGGAAGACAUUAAAUGUAUUUUAUUAGUGCAGUUUUUAAAGACAAAGAUAAAUAUUAAAAUUCAACUCCCCCCAAAACCCAAUAUGGAUGUGUUUUGGUAGAUAUGAUGAGUAACAGUUGAAAGUAAAAAUCAAAUAAGAUAUGAUAAUUAAUGUUAAUAUGGUAUCAGUGAUCAUCUGUAGUCAGUUUAUACAAACUUAUUAAAGAUUAUUUCACUUCAUACCAUUUUUCAAUUUAUUUCGCUUAAUUGAAUUAGAGGUGUGUGUGUGUGUGUGUGUGUGUGUCUGUGCGUGUGCGCACGCGCACACCCCAUGCUUUAGGAAGGAGGCACAGCAGUUUUGGGGAAAAUGUGUGUGUGGCCCCAGCUGCCUGAUUUUUCUCUGAGAGUCAGAAGUGGUGUCUGAGUACAUACAGGUUAGGAAUCCCCAAGGUCUGUCUUCCUUUAGCUACUACCAGCCCCCAUCUUCCUCCAGGACUAAUAUUUUUUAAACCUUAGUGCAAGGACCUAUCCCCCCCAGACUAAAUACUGAUUAUCACAAGAGAUCUUGCUUGCUAGCUCUGAAUGGACUUGUGGACCAGGUCCCUUGAUAAACUGUAGUGGGGGUUCCAGUAAUACAGGCCUCUUUCUUACAACAGCAAAGAAUCCCCAAAUGAGGAGACACUUUGCCCCACAAGUCACCAUGGUUUUGGUGCUGAUGGUUACUUUCCUUCUGUAUUAGAAUCCUCUCUACAUACAGCUCUUGCUAUAUUUAGUACCCACCAGGAUCCCCUGGAAUUCAUAAGCAUGUGGUUUAUGUUGUAUCAUUGCAAUGUGGUUCAUGAAGCCUUAGGGCCAGGAGUCCUGGAUUCUGGUUUUUGUUCUGCUCCUCUGGGAUGAGUGACCUUGGAAAUGUUGCCUUCCUGAUUCUUUCCUUUGUAGAAGGGCACUGCAAAUAGCAUCUGCCUCCGGAUUGUUGUGAGAACUAAAUGACAUAAUGCCUAGGUGCGUAGGUCUGUUUUAGGCACAUACGAAGUUCUCAGUCAGUGAUACUGAAAUCAAUGUUUAUAUAGUCAGUGUAUACAUUAUAUACAAUGAAAUCAGUGAAUUAUUAUUGACACUUCUAAGGUGUUGUCUAACCAGUGGGAGCGUACACCCAGUGUACUAUUCUUUCUUCUUCUUUGUAGCCCCUAGAACUAUAACAUCAGGGAGUCUAUAAACAAUAGAUAAGUUAGCUACCUCAACGGUAAUCACUUCACUCAUAUAUAUCACAAAAAUAAACAAAAUAACCUACUUCUAGGAAGUAUAAGUAGAUAAUAUUGAACAUUGCUAAUGCAAUAAAAAUAACCCUUAUUUACUUUGCUUCCUUAAAUCGCAUAUCAAAAUAAGAAGAUACUAAUUUGGACUUUCCUCUAUCUUUCCAAAAUUUUAAAGCAUUCCCAAAUUUGCCUCAUUAGCUCUAUCACUCCAGGCACACUUCCUCAUCAAUUGAACUUACCUCAAAACGAAUUCAUGAUAUAUGCCAAUAAAAUCAUUCACUAGCAUCUUCCCAUUGUCACCAUAUCUAACAUUUAAGAAAUAAAAAUGGGCCGGGUGCGGUGGCUAACGCCUGUAAUCCCAGCACUUUGGGAGGCCGAGGCGGCGGAUCACGAGGUCAGGAGAUCGAGACCAUCCUGGCUAACACAGUGAAACCCCGUCUCUACUAAAAAUAUAAAAAAUUAGCCGGGCGUGGUGGCGGGCACCUGUAGUCCCAGCUACUCAGGAGGCUGAGGCAGGAGAAUGGCGUGAACCCGGGAGGCGGAGUUUGCAGUGAGCCGAGAUUGCGCCACUGCACUCCAGCCUGGGCGACAGAGUGAGACUCUGUCUCAAAAUAAAUAAAUAAAUAAAUAAAUAAAUAAAUAAAUAAAUAAAUAAGGCAUGACAAUUUAAUAGAAGAUCAUUACUGCUCAGUAUUGGUCAGGCUUCUUCCUAAUUCUAAGCAAACUCAACAAAGCAAUUGUUCCCACAGCCUAGGGUUUUCACUUUUAUCCUCGUAGUGUUUAUAUUGCAUGAAGCCUUCCUGAACAGCACGUCCAUAUGCUCGCCGCUGAAAUCACUAGGAAAUGUCCUCCUCACCAAUGAGGUGUGAGAAAGGAGGAAAGCAGGAGUGUUUAUUUUUUACAUCUUUUUUUCUGUUACCUUUUUUUUCUCCUUUGAACAUAUUUAUAUUCUCAAAUAUUCACUUUCAUUGGAAAUCUUUGACAUUCUAAUAUAACAUGAGGCAAAUCAGUGCAGACUCAAAUAGGUUACCAAGAUACAGGCCUGUGACAUAUUAGAUUUUCUCUUUUCCACAAUUUCAAAAAUCAUUACUUUAUGAUUCAAUUUAGGAAGCAUUUGAAUAAGUACUUGAAUCUAACACUACUAGAGGCUUCAGGGAUUCCCCCCAAAACAUUAAAAUGGUUCUUGCAAUCGAGGAAAUUCAAAUUUCAUUGCUGCUUAUGAGACGUGUAAGAUUAAAUGUCAAAAUAUAUGAUAAACAUGCUAUAUAUUAAUACCAUUCAAGGUCAGAGUUGGGAGAGAUCAGAAUGAUUCAGAUAUUUGAAGAUGGUUUCAUUGAAUAAUAAACCUGUAAAUAUAUGAAACAUUUGAAGGGUAUUUGAAACCUAACGAUGGUUGUUUUAUAUUAUAUGGAUGAGAGAUAGAACAGAUAAAGGCAAAAAUGAACUGUAUUCAUUUUAUUAUUACCUUUUACUAAAGUAUUUAACCAAGUGCUGUUGACAUGAAAAACCAAGAAUGUACAUCUCUGUCUGUUCUUUUCUCUGAGCAUCGCCGGAUUCCCGUGUUAAUGAAUAAUGAAAUGGAUAGAGUCUGUAUAGUGUAGUGCAGUUUAUGCCAGAAAUAGAGUGUAAUGGUAAGAACAAAGGCUUUGGUGUUAGACAAUGCGGUAUUGUAUGUUAUUUUUGACAUUUACUGCCUUUCUAAUGUUGGAAAAGUUACUUAAUGUCACUGAGUCUCAUUUUCUCUUUUAGGGUGGUUCUAAGAGUUAAGUAAGAUAAUAAAUGAAAAGUGCCUAGCAGAAUGCAUGGCAUAGAAUAUGCAUCAAUACAUAGAAAUUUGACCGUCACUUGAAUUAAGAGACUGGUUUAGGAGCAUUGUAAUCUUAUGCAAUAAAAUCUUAGUGGCCUUUAAAAAAUUUUUUUUAUUUUUUUGAGACAGGGACUCACUCUGUCACCCAGGCUGGAGUGCAAUGAUGUGAUCUCAGCCCGCUGCAAUCUCUGCCUCCCAGGCUCAAGUGAUCCUCCCACCUCAGCCUCCCAAGUAGUUGGGACUAUGGGCGUGUACCACCAUGCCUAACUAAUUUUUGUAUUUUUUGUAGAGACAAGCUCCCACUAUAUUGCCCAGGCUGGGCUCGAACUCUUCAGCUAAAGAGAUCCUCCCCUCUUGGCAUCCCAAAAUACUGGGAUUACAGGCAUGAGCCAACACACUCGCCAUUCUCAUUUGUUAUUUGUAUUAAGAGAAAAAUAUCCGUUUACCAAGGUGUAACCUCAAUCUCCAGGGCUGAAGCUUGAUCCUCCCACUUCAGCCUCUUGAGUAGCUGGGACUACAAGCAUCCAAUACCACUCCCAGCUAUUUUUUGUUCUUUUUCAUCUUCUUCUUUUUUUUUUUUUUUUUUUUUUAAAGGAGACAAGGUCUUGUUAUGUUCCCCAGGCUGGUUUCAAACUCCUAGGCUCAAGAGAUCCUCCUGCUUCAGCCACCCAAAGUUCUGGGAGUACAGGCAUGAACCAUUGCACCUUGCCCUCCUGUAUACUUUAAAUCAUUUCUAGAUGACUUAUGCUACCUAAUACAAGGCCUACACAUUUUUUUCAUUUGAGUGGGUUCGAUGUAGCACUUGGCACACAUGAAAUUCAAGUUUGGUAUCUGGGACUUUUUGGAAUUUUUUCUGAAUAUUUUUGAUGCACUGUUGGUUGAAUCCAUUAAUGCUGAACCCACGGAUACAGAGAGCAAUUGUAUUUUGACAUCUGCCAGGGUGUGUGUGUGGUGGUGGUAGGAUAUUUUUCCCAUGGAAUUUGGCCAACACUAUAAAUAAGGAAUUUUUAUUUUUUCAAGAGCUGGUUUAUAGGCAUAGUGCUGAAUAAAAGAGACAAAUGAUUAAAGAAAGAAUAACAAUAAAGUAUGCUACAAAACAUAAUAUAGUGUUACAAUGUCGUCUUUGCAAGGACAUCUAAACCAGCCAGGGAGGUCAAGGAGAGCAUCUCCUUUCAAAAGCAGUAACAUCUAAAUUGACCUCUGAAAAAUGCUAGGAUUUGCCAUGAAAAGAGUGAGGAUAAAAAUAUUUGAGGCAGAAAGAAACAAUGUGUGUGAAGUUCCAAAACUAAGACAGGAUUGUUCUUUAGUCAACUGAGUUCAGUAGGGUUAGAGCUUAGACUUCAAGGGGAGUUAGAGAUGUUUGGGAACGACGAGAUUGAAAUAUUAAGAGAGACCAAGGAAGGGCUUAGUAAACUAUGUUUCAAAGGUUUAUUUUUGAGCACAAUUCCAUGUUGAAGGUGCUCAUCAUGGAAUCAAGACUUAUCUCUGAGCGUCAUCUUUGCUAUGCUCACGUUAUAAUAAUGAUUUUUACAUUUUGGCAGUGCCACAGCAGUGUCCUGGCAUGUGGUAUGAUCAUUCAGCCAUCUAUGACAAUGUAAUUAUAAUACAUUCUUUUUAUUAUGUAUCAUAUGUGUUAUUUUGUAGUAAAGGUCUUUGUGAAAUUCAGUAUGCUGAGUGUCUGAUCAUAGUAACCCUUUCAAAAUUAGAAAAUAAAAUCAGUUUGGCAUGAUUUCACUAAAAGUCACCCCUUUUCUCUCUAAGUGCUAAUUCUGUGUUAUAUCAGUUAUGGUUUUACCAGAAAAAAAUUAAGGUCGCCAUUGUGUUGUUUCUAGAUUUCACUCUUUUUUAAAAAAAUUGGGCAACAUUUGCUUUCAGAUUCUCCAGACACUGUAUUAGCAUUCGUCAUUCUCGUAUCUUUUACUCACCCGGGCUGCUUCUUACCUGGGCCAGUAACCGGAACUUCUCUGGUCUCUUAUUAUCAUUUUCUCUCUUUUGGGCCCUCCUUUUAUCUUAAUCGUAUUUAUUCUAUCAUAGUCAUUGUUAAGAGCGUUUAUCUUAACAGAAAAAAGAAAAAGAAAACAGGAGCUGAGGACUUAUGCUCUCUCUCUCUAAUUUUGUUCUACUUUAUACAAUUCUACCAACUUACCACGGAAUCACAGACUCCUUAUCCUUUUUAUCAAAUAAUUUGAAUUAUGUGGAACCAAUUCUUAUUUUUGUUAUUUGAUGCACUACAGCCACUCUUUAAAAACUGCUGUAACUCAACCAGAGAAGGAUAUAUCUUUAAAAAUGUUUCUGGACCAGCCACCAGUUUCUUAUCUCUCAAGUGGUAGUACUGGGGAAGAUUUGCAAAAUAGCCCCCAGAAAAUUAGGAUCUGUGCAUAUUUAUAAGAGGUUAGAUUCUAAGACAAACAUGAAAAUUUCAUAUUUGUGAUUUCUGAAAAUUGUUGAAUGCAAUCUUGAUAUAUUUAUUUAUUAAGUAGAUAACGAAUAGCUAAAUUAAAAGGUUAUGCAAAUGUAAAAUAAUUGCAGAAACAAUUCAUAUUCAAAUUUACGUUUUGCUGUAUUAUUUCCUGAAUAUAUAUCAUUUUAUUAACAUUAUCAAGUGCAAAUAAUUAAACUGAAAUUUAUAAUAUGUAAAAUAUUUUAAUAGAAAUUGAGUUUUGUGGUUAAAAAAAACCUAAUUUUCCCAGAAAAAUAAUAUUUAAAUUCACUUUGGCAUUCAAAAAAUAUUAGGCUAUUCCUAAUGGGGAGAAACCUGGUAACUGGGGUUUAACCCUUUCAGUAUGAGCUGUAAUUGAAUGUAAAUUGUAAAGCAGUUGUCUUGCAUAGAGUGCAUUUGAAAAAAAAAAAAAGACCCUGAAAAAGUCUCAUCUCUUUGACUUUUUAAUGUAUAAUUCUAGCGUUUCAUUUUACAAAAAGUAUAAACACUUCUAAAUCCUACUCAUUUCAAUAGAAUGUCUCUGUUUUCCAUGAGGUACCAGAAAAAGCCUUAAAUGAUAUGUGAUGUGCUGCUAGUCGUUUAAUGAGACAUUCAAUGCAGUAUGAUUAUGACUCUGUUGCUCAGUCAUUUCAAGUUCUGUCCAUCAAAAUUGUGGGCACUUGCUUCUCAAAUGAAUCAAAAAGAGUUUCCAGGACCAGGGAGAUAUAAGUAUUGAAACAGUAAGCAACACCCAUACCAUAAAGUAGAAGUGAUUCAUUGGUUAACAGAAAACGUAAUGUCCAGAGCUUCAUGGUUAUAGAUAAAAUAGGCUAUGUUUAUUUAUCCAUUUAGGGUAGUUUUUUUUUUUCAUUUCGUUCCAGGUUAAUUUUGAUUUCCUUUGUAAUAACGGGAAAUUAUUUUGAGAUAGGCUUGUUGGUAUCCUUGAUUAUCUGUGUGGUGUCUGCAUGAAAGAGGAAACAAGUAGAUUUUCAGGAAGUUUUCUUAAUAGUUCAAUGCAAUCAGACUGGCCAAUAUUGAGAAUUACUGCGCCAUAAAUAAUUGUGGUUGGUUUCUAACUUUGAUUUUAUUCAGCCUAAUAACAAGUAUUGCUCUAUAGAUAAUUGUUGACGGUUGCAGACUCUGAUUUCGUUCAAUUAAGCUGGUAACCUUUUUAAGAAACUGCUUGGGAGAAAGCCAAGAAUUCCAGUGAACUGAUUUCUAGGGGGACUGAAUUGAAAUUGUGUUAGCUUCAAAAAUGUUUCAUGUAGGUCCAGCUGUGUUAAUUAACCUUUUCCUUAAACUACCCUCUCCACAAUUGGAACCCCAAAUCGGCAAACAUAGCAAAGGACCAUUUUAUCUAGAUUUAGGUUUUUCUCAAAGUGAUUAUAAACUUGGAAAGACAUUAUAAAAUAGGUUUUUGACAUAUAGUAAGUGUAUGAGGGCUGCUCCUUCUUUCUAAAUCACAGAAAAAUUCAGAUUCUCUCUCCUUCCCUUUCUUCCUUUUUAAAAAUCACCCAUGUAUGUAUUCAAGAAAAGUAAAACCAGUGUAUAUUACACAAAGGUUUGCUUUCUUUAUGUCAAAUUGUUAAUUUAUAAUGGUAAAUACUGUGCUUGGAAGACAGUAGGAAACUCUAUCAAACGUGCCCUUUACUAAUAAAGUAGAGAAUUGUCAUUUAGAGUAGUAUACUUGACCUAUGGCAAAUACUGCUAGUACUGGAAUUCCAUUGUUUAUCUCUUGUGCUCUACACAGUGGGAGGGAAAAAGAGAUGCAUUGUAUUGAAAGUAUACAUUAUGCUUGGGAAAAAGUGUUUCUUUAAAUAAACAAAACCUUUUCAGUAAGUACCAGUACAAGCUAAGAAGGCCAAGGUCAUAGGUCUCAGUAACCAUGUAUGUCAGUAAAAGGCAUCUUGUGUGUUUCGUGGUUACAGUUGGUCUAUAAAGUUGUAUUUUUGGUCACCCAAGUAAGAGGCAAGAGAGCAUUCGUAGGAUUUCCUACUUGGAAAAGGUAGGGAAGAAAAAAAGAAAAGUGAGAAGACAAAAUUACAAACUUCAAAACAUGCUUAUUUGAUGAUCAGUAGUAGGUGUUAUCUUUGUAUACAGAAUCUUUGGGCUGAUUUUCGUUAAUUGUAUCAACUUGAGUAAUAGUUCUUAUUUCUGGGAAAUUAGAAUCUACCAAAGAACAGCUUGGGAAAAAAAACCUGUUAAUACUGGGUUUCAAUACGUGAAGCUUUGUCAUUUGCUGAUGAUCUUUAUUCAUCACAUUCACAAUUCACAAGAUUAUUUCUAAGGUGGGUUUGAUUUACUGACUUUUCCCAUGCUCCAUGAGAGCUGCCAUAUGCCUGAUGAUUCUGGGCUGUCUCUUCUAGGUUUUUUAUCCACCCCUUGAUAGCAACAGUUACUUCCUAUAUCCCUGGGACAACUAAGCGGAGGACAGUAGUUAACUAAAGUGGCUUUGAACAGUGGCAGAAAAAUGUGCUGGGAAUACCUUAUAUUCUAAGCAACCUCCAAUUUCUGUGAGCUAAAAGUGCUAUGUAAUGUGAUAAAGAAUAUAACAUCAGGAGUUUUGUUUCAGGAGAAAAAAGUGAGAUAAUUGGCUGAAAUGGACAAGUUUUGAAAUUUACUAGCCUUGAGCAAUGAUGAAUAACUGAAAGUGCUGAAUCAAACUGGCCUUUGAAUUAAAGCAAUAUAACAUACUGUAGAGGUUCGUCAUUUCCAGCAGAUAGGAGGUCCUGGCACACACAGUAAGAUAAUGUGAAGAAUUAGCUUCAAUCUAUGAUUUUUGACCUUCAGUACAAGUCUAACUUAAAAUAUAAUCUUCGAAAUUUGCAUUUUGGAAUUUGUCUUUUCCCUGUUCCUUGCAAAACCACAUACAUCAAUAUACAUUGAUAUGUGGGGAAAAUGAUCUACAGUGGUGUAAAUUUAACAUGCAAUUCUGGAAUACUAACUUUUGAAUUUCGCAUAUUUAAGUCUUUUUAUAUUUCUAGAAUUUUCAUACAGGAUGUGAUAACUUGAUAACAAACUCAACAGUAAUUUGCACCAUUUCAGGUAACCUACUGAUUAAAUUUUUUUAUACUUUAUAGUUAUUCUAACAAUGAUUCCAUUUUCAGAGAGGUUCUCUGGGCUUUCUGCUUCAUGCCUCCUCUAGCCACCCUGAACGAUUAUAUCCUAAGGGUCCGUAUUCUAAAGGUUUUCUGACACUGGCCUUGGUUCUCCAUUUCAUGAUCUUUCUGACUUUAGACAGAGAUGUUUUCUAGGCUUUUUCUAUGCCUUACUUCUCUUACAUCUUUAAAUGCAUUUGUAGAUACUUUUAGAUUAAAUUGUGCUCAAACAUAUUCAUAAAGCAGAACAAACAGCUGACUUAUAUUUGGGAGGACUUUUACAUAGUGGGAGUUCUAGACUCUAAGAACAUGCCAUUCAAUUUUAACAUCACUUCUAUUGAAAAAAGAGAUUUAUCAUGUAUUGCUUUGAUUUACCACAUCCUUACUGGAUGUUUGUGGACAGAAUUUGUAGAUAGGAAAUGUUCUGCAGUGGAUCCCAUAUUGAAAUUUGUGGAUUCCAUUUGAGAUUUACAGACUAAUAUAAAAACAUAGCGAUACAAAUUUAAUGACAUAAUUCUGAGUGUCAUAAUUGUCAUUUCGAAUUUAAUGCUUAUUCUUAUAGAAUGAAAAUUGUUUUAUAUGUAAGGUAAAUCUAAGCCUUCCAAAUAUAUUUUAUGCUUAAUACAAACAUCUUUUUGUUCCAAAUUAGAGUAGUCCAGUAAUUGAAGUAAGCCAGAACUAAUGUCAGUGCCAUCAUUCUUUAAUAGUAAAAUCAUAGGAACGUUGCUGCAAUAAGGUAGUGGAGAGUUCAAAAUCAUAAUUUCAUUAAUGGAAAUAUGCUGGACUAUCACUAAUCAAUUUAUUUUUGUUUAGUUUUUAAUAGUAUUUUUCCAAAUAUUUUAAAUUUAGUCUUAGUAUUAGACUUUGUCAAAGUAUUAUAAUACUGAGCCUAAUAGUAGGUUUGAUGUAUUGAAUGUCAUACUUAAAACAUAUUUAAAAGAUUUAAGCAGAUUCAAAAUAAAUAAGUAGCAUAAUGAAAACAGUUAUAGUGCUAGCUGAAAAAUUAAACUUUCAAUUCCAUUGGACUAUAUUCAUAAUAACCUUUUCUAAAAACAAAAUAAAUGUCGAAUGUAAUGAAUUGCCAGAAUGUGAUAUUUAUGAAGCAUCAAUCAGCAUUUUCUUAUUUUCAAGGAAGGUCAUAGCUGCAACUUAGCAGGAAUAAAAGUCUCUGCUCCCUCCCCUAAGAAGGAUUCAUGUGUGUUAAAUAAGAGUCACACAGAGAGAAUACCUGUAACCCUACUGUACCAUCAUUGAGCUCAGAGACUGGCUAACUUGCAAGCACCUUCCUAUUUUCCACUACCAUGCUAUAUCAUCCCUAGAAAGUUGAGGAAGCACAGAUGGAUUCAUUUGCACCUACAGUGUCAGCUUUCUCAUCUUUCUUUUGAUUUUAGCUUUCCUAAAAACCACUCUCAACAUUACAGCACAGAAUAGAAUGAACAUUUACUGUGAAUUGAUAUUGUAAGUAUGAUUAAUAGGGAUGGCUGCCCCUUUUCCUGAUAUCAUGAUUCAGUAACAAAUAAACAAAGAUGCCUUAUUUUCUCUUUUCCCGCCUCUCUCUCAUGUACUGGCAUACAAAAACUGUGAGCCUCUCAAUAAAAAGGCAGGCUGUACAUGAACUUAAUCACUGUAUCUAUUUCAGAGAAGAUAUCUGUCUCAAAUUGGAGUUAGGGUAUGGAGAGUUUUAGUUGACUUCACUUUUUUUUAUUUUAAAGUUUUGAUUAGAGUACUAUAAUUAUAAAAUAGGUAGCAUAAUUAUAUCUACAAAGUGAUGUUGAAAAUACUUUAAAAAAUAAAACAUCCUAAUCAAGUAAGUUUUAUGGAAGUAUAGGAGCAGGCUUUUAGCACAAAAUCUUGGGAAGGAAAAAUAGAUAUCUGACCUUAAAAUUUAUAUAUAAUCAUCACAUUGGCCAACGUGCCAUUUUUAAAUGACUCCAUGUAAAUGUAUGACUGGUUUUCUCAAACACGGAUUCAAGUUCAUAACAUUUAUUUUCCUUUUAAUAUGCAUCUAAAUUACUAACUGACCAAAACAAAAUAAAGUAUUGGUAACUUGGGGGGAAAUUUCUGUCUCAGUAAGCUAACUAAUUGCUUCAAUUAUUUCAAAAUUUUUUCCUAUUUUUAAAGGAAAAAGUCCAAUUUUUGGUGCAAAAGUCACAGGCCUAAAAGUGCAAUUUGAAAUAACUGCAGCAGCUUUUUUCCUCUGAUUUUAUUUCUUCUUUCUAUGUAGAUGCAAAAUGCAAAAUUUAUCUCAAGAGGAAUAGUUAUCUUUUAUUUGCUGAUUAAGCUAACCAAAUAUACAUCUUAUUAUUUUGUUUUGUUUUAGCCCAGGGUCUAAUAAAGUUGUAUAAGAAUUUCUUGGGCCUCAGCCAUUUAUUUGAGGUAAAUACUGUGGUUUGAGAAAAAUUUUCAUGUAACUUAAUUUCCUGAGGAAAUGAUCUAUGAAAUAUUUAACAUCUAGUUGCUAGCAUACUUUUUAGUGCUAAUAACCAACUCCAAAGAGAAAGAAAUGGCAUUCUUUUUCAUUUUAUUCCAGUGGUGUGUGGCAUGUUAAAAUAUGACACAUAUUUGGAAAAAUACAUUAUAUAAAAUUAAAUGUUAAACCUGUAAUGCAUCAUUUGAUUGAUUGAGCAAGAUAAUUUCUUGAGAAACAUUGCUACUAGAUUAUGGAAAAUAUAUGAUCAAGUUGUUAAGAUGGCAAAAACCUACAUUAAUUCUUUAAAACUAGGGACAUUUAUGUAUUUGGAGAGCACUAUUGGGAAAAUAAGUAAUUGCGUCAACUCAUUCAUCAUUUGCCCUUUAUACUUAGAGCUUUAAGAAGAGAAUGGUAAGUGAUACUAUAUCCACUCUUUCUUUGGCAUUCAGACAGUAACUUGUUCAAUUAAAAAUUCUUGUUAGGUCAGACAUAAUGGAUUCUUGUUGUUACUUUAGUAUUUAUUCAAUGAAAGAGAUCAAUAUUUUUGGCCCCAAGGGAGCUGCACUGAUAAGAGACUCUGCAGUAAGUCUCUCUGUUCAUUAUAAACUUUUGGCUGGCAGGUGCAGUGUCUGCUGUAUGACCAGUUUUAAUUAGAACAUCAAGGUAGAAUGAGAAUUCAGACAUUCUUUUUCUCUCUUUUUAAUAGCAUAUAUGCUUUUUAAUAGCUUUUUGCCUUCUCCUUCUUCCUUUUCUCUGGUGUGUGCCCUUUUUAGAAGGUAUUUCUUAAAGGGAAUUUGAGAACAAUAGGUCUGAUUUUGAGAAAUUUAACUAUUAUCCACUUGAUCGCAUGUGUUUCAAGUUUGAGUAGAUUAAAUCUGAUGAUGGUUGUGUAGCCUCAUUGUACGAGACAGGUAGAGAAAUAAUCAUCUUUCAUUAUCAUGCCCACCUUUGCCAAGUUUUUAAUGUAUCUGUGUUUAAAUUUAAUGGAACUGAUUUGUGAUUUUUUUGGAAACAUGACAUUAAAUAAAGCCAUAAAAAACUCUAUUUUGCUUUGCAACUUCAAAUGCUUUCUAAAUAUGGCCUAAUGCUCUAUUCAAGUAACAAAGUCGUUUGCAGAAUAAGCUGUCACAUUCAACAAGCUCUAAUUUUGGCUAGAUCUAUUAUUUUACAAAUUAAACGAAGGUGCAGGUCUCUGCCUUCCCCGCAACAAAAUCUUAACCAGACUAUCACAUUUAAUCUGCUAGAUGAUUUAUUAACUUGCCAUUUAAUUCAUUUCAUUAAAAUACGUAAUUCAGUUUAUAGAUUUGAGAGCUGGCAGAAUCUUUUACAAAUCAUUUAGUUUUGCCCCUUUCUUUUACAGAUAAAGAAACUUGAGACCAAGAGAAAUUAAAUGGCAUGCUCAAAGUUACAUGUCAAAUGGUUGCUACAGAAACCAGCUCCUCUAAUUUAGUUCUCUUUCCAAAUAGCAUGGCAAAGACAUUUGUUACUAUAUAUAAAAAACAAUACUUGUUUAAAUGUAUUUAUUAAUAGACAUACUGAUUUGUUUUCAUACCCCAAUUUACUUAGAGGUAUCAUAAUACAAUACAUAAUGAUUUAAACCUGUGGGACAUGCAAAAAGGAAUCAUGUUUAAAGGUCAGAAUACAUAAAGGUUAAAUGUCAGAGGCCCAGAAAUAAGAGGUACAGCUUUUAAGCCUAAACUUUAAAUUGUAGGCUCUGUAAGUGCCAGGACCAUGUUUUCUAGGUUUUCAUAAAAGUAAACCUUAAAGGUCCGAGAACUCACAGAAUAUUGUUGCCUGAAUAAUUAAAUAUUCCAAAGAAGGUGAGAAUUUCAGAGAAUUUUACUUGUUACUAACACCAGUAUUUCCCACACUGGAAUAAUACUAUUUGUUUACUUUUCAGUUAACACUCUUAAUAUGAAAAAAACCUGCUUAUUUGAAAUUAGACAUUUCCUGAAGCAUAUCUGUCUAGUCAAAAAAGGUCCUAAUCAUAUUAGGAGAGUGGCAAUUAUAGUAGUUUAGACUUUGCGUAUAACAUAGCGAUACAUUAGAGGAAAGAAGUAUAAAAUGCCGAGGCAGGAAAUUAUUGUUAUCAGAAGUAUAUUUAUACUACUGUGGCCAUUAGGCAGACUAAACAUAAGAAUGACCAAGAAAUGGAAAAUAUCCUCACACCUGCCAUUUAUAACAGCUAAUACAUAUGGAGUCUACUGCUUGCCAUGCCCAAAGCACCUGAUUUUCUCUUUAUGACUUUACUGAUCAGUUUUUGCAUUGUCUGUAAUCAUGUUGAGACUUCAUUUUGGAAGACCUGAUACUGUUGUUUUCUAAGUUCAAAUAGAAAAGGGUAAUAUUCAUAUGGCACUUUUGUACUUUGGAAAACUCUGUCUCAUAAUAAGCUGAGGAAACCUGUGGUUACAGGAAAGAAGAGUAAACAGUAUCAGUUAUUGAGAGCCUCCUAUAUGAGAGGCAUGUGAGACACCUUCCCUUAGAAAAUGGUAAAGGAAGGUAUUAGUGUUCUUAAAAAAAUAAUAGUAACAGGGAAAUCUAGCUAUGAAGUGGCAGAAUUCAAAUCUAGGUCUUCAGAGUUGAAGUCAGGCCUAUAGACUCAAGUGACUUCCGGGGCCAGGGAGGAAAAAUGAAAUUGUGAAAUUUAUAUGUCUUGUAAAUCUUUGCUCUUCACAGUUGUAUAGCAUUGAAUGUCUAAGGCCUUGCUCUUCAAGACUUGACAGAAAUGACUGUUACCGUGUUUUUCAAAUGUCUCAUCUCACAUGAGGUUAUGCAUUAUAGCAUUAAGAACUAUAACUCCCCUAGAGCUAUUUGUGGCUUAGAAUAAGAGUUUUGUUAAGAUUUCUUAGUACUUUAGACCUUAAAUGGAAAAAAUUGCAAAGUGAAAUCUAUCUUAUGGUACAUAGUGCUUUUAUACACACAUCAAUGUGAAGUAGUUCUUUAUGAGAUUGAUUUUGUAGCAUUGAACAACAACAACAAAAAGUAAAUUACUGAAGGCUGAGACAGGUAAGGAAACAGAGAAGUCUACCCACAUUUCUGAACUCUUUGCUGAAGGCAGCUGUGUCCUAGAACUUACUAGUUUAUGACAGACUAUACACUGCUUUUGAACUGUUUCAGAUUACUCAGAAACAGCAUUCAUGGCCAGCCCAGAAUUAAUGUGUAAAUGACCUUUCACAGAACCAGGAUGGAGGAAGACGUCACUUAACUUUGGAAGAGGUGGAUAUUUAGAUGUCAUGAACAUCUCUAGGCUUCUCUUAGAGCUAAAUAGUAAAAGGGUUUCCCUUUCAUAAAUCUUCAUUCUCUUUAUAGAAUGAAUGGGUGAUAUAUAGUUCCAUCUACUUCUAGAUGCUUGCUGUUCAUUUGUGUGAUGUUUAAUGCAAAGCAAGAGGAAGGAAAAUGUAGUUCUUUAACAAAGAUCUUUUCAGUAUAUGUUAAAUUUACCACUAGAGAUGAAAAUACAUUGUUUUUUAAGUGUUUGAUUUUGUGAGGUCUUUGGGUAGUGGAAUCAAUUCACAGUCAGUUCCAUGUAAUUUGGAUAUGUGAUUAUUACUUAGAAUCCCUGAUUUCUCUAAGUUGUAGUUUCUUAUAAGACACUAAAACAUUUUACUUUAUCAUGCAGAUGAUUUCUUAUGCAAAAGCAGUGCUCUGUAGUGCUUCUACAGAGUUUACAAAAAAUGGUUUCAUGAUACUAAUUUUUAAAGUUUUAUGUGUCAGUUUUUUUAAUUUUAAUGACAAAAUUUUCAUGACAAAAAAAUCAGUAUAUGGAAGUCAUCAGCCCUAGGUUUUAAAAGUAAGAAAAGAAAAUGGGAAAUAGAGUAAUAUCUUACUUUUUUCAAGAGAAAUAAAAGAAAAUUAAUUGGUAAGAAUAAUAUUGCUUUCACUUCUUAUAUAAAUCUAAUGUCUAUAUCUGCCCUGCAUUUUAUGUAAUGAGGACUAUAGGACAGAUUUUACUUUAUGAGCAUUCAUUUUAAAUUAAAAUAAUAACGUAGUCAUGAUUUUCAUUAAUUAGAAAUGCCCUAUUCUAACAUUUCCUCAGACAGCAUGGAAUACACUGCUAUGGCCUCUAGUAGGACUCUUCAGUGUGACGCUAAUUAAAACCAACAUUGAUUCUGCUGUUUUAUUGACAUACAUCAAAUUUAGAAUGAAAAGUAGCUUUUGAGUGACUUUAAUUGUCAAAACUAUUGAAUUAAUUUUGAUAUUUCUGAGGAAAUGAUCUUCAUUUAAAGUAAAACUUACUGAGGGUUUGUGUAAUCAAAUGCCUAUCAAAAUACUUGAUAUUCCUGUAUAAAACAUGCUCUACUAAAGUAGUAUGUUGAAGAUAAGUCAAAUCAGCUUUUAGCUAUUGUGUGGUAUUCUGGAGAGGUGUAGGACAUUGUAAUGUGGAUCCUAGACUCAGAGUGGCUGGGUUUGCCUCAGUCAUGCUAGCUGUGUGACUUUGGGUAAGUUACCUACACUCUCUACUACUCAGUAUUCUUAUCUGUAAAUAGGGGAUGAUGAUAAAACCUAGGUAGGAUUGUUGUGAGACUGGAAUGAGUUUUAUGUAAAUGCUUAAUACAAUUUCUGAGCUGUUAGCUCUUUUUAUUUUUGUUGUUGCUAUCGUUUUUAACACAGAGUAAGGAGACAUGAUGUACUCAGGACCAGAUUUUAGUUUACUGUUGUUGGAUUUUUGUGUUUUGCCAUGGAAAAUAAUGUUUAAAUAAGACCACUGUCAUCACGCUGGAGCUCUGUUUUCCCUAAGUACGGUAUUUGAAAGGAAUUACGCAAUAUAGUGUCUUUUCCCAGCUGGGAGAGGCAAGUCACUGCUUAGAUGGCCGGUCCUGGAUAUGAAGAAAUUUGGUCUACUCAGUGUGAGUGACAUAUUUACCCUCCUCCACCAUGAAUGUGCCCAUGCACUUAGCCAUUUCUGCAGAGUUGCACAGAUUCUGUACUUGCUGAAAAAUAUGCUUGCAUGGAAAGGCCUUGUGGCGUAUUUUGUGGCAUUGAAUUGCUACCAUCUGUUUCCUAGCCAACGUUAAAAGAAAAAGAAAAAAGAAGAAGUAGCAUUAGAAAAUGUGCCAUUUUACAAGUGCUACAGUAAAAUUUUUUUUACACUUCAUUCCCUACCCUCGAAUAUGUGGAUGUAAGAGUGGCUUCAGAUACUUUCAGAUUUAUCAAUUCACAGCUGCAUUUAAUAAAACAUUUGAAGUUUAUCACAAAUGCUUUCACUGUUAACUACUACUUCCCCGCACCCCGUGGAAUUGGUGGUGCAAGUCUUAAUUACAUUUUGUGUUAUUGACUAAUAUAUAUUUUAAUAUUUAUUUUAAAGAUAUUUCUUCCCACAACGAUAUCUGUUCCUAGGCAUAGAAGAAUGGCAUUUUAAGAGAAUUUGACAUAGUAACUAUUAAUAGCUUGAAAACUGAAAAUUCUGACUCUUACAAUAAAGACUCUAUUGUCUUUGG